UGCAGUGAGCUGAGAUUGCGCCACUGCGCUCCAGCCUGGGCGACAGAGCGAGAUUACGUCUCAAAAAAACCAAAACUGCUGGCCCCUCCAGAGGGUCCAGGAUACUGAGCUCCUGAGCCUGGGAUCCACGCGCAUGUGGUCUGUCUGCACACUGGCACCGCAGAAGGGUUGGCAGGCGGGCAGGCAUGGCUGGAGACCCCGCUCAGAUGAGGCGGCCACUCCAGGGCAGUGCCAUGCUGGACAGAAGGGACUGCCUUGGAAGUGGGACAGACCCCAGACCCUUGGGGUGGGGGCCCUGCAGGGGAGGCCUUGAGGAGGCGCCGGGUCUACAGGCCCCUGUGUGCUCACAUCCCAGCCCCCGGGGAGAGGUGGGAGUGGGUGGGCGCACCCAGCUCCCCUGUCCAGGCUCGUCCCCCUUGUUGGGGCAGCCCUCAGCAAGUGGGGGGCUGGUUCCAGGCACAAGAAGUGAGGCCAGGGAGGAAGCCCUGCCUGUGUUCAGCCCAGUUGUGCCCCAACUCAGGUGGGCUUCCAUGAGGGACAGCCUCUGGGAGGGUGGGGGUUUGUGGGCCAGGGCUGGAGAGCUGCCUGGCUGUGCUAAAAAUACCGGGCAUGCUGCAGACAGGUGCCAGUCUGGGGCACAGGCUACCCUGUCUCAGGCUGAUGGCCUUGGCACUCCACCCCACUGCCCCUGUGACGCGGGGGCCGCCAAGGCUUGGUCUUGAUUCCCAGAGGCCCUGCUGGUGACCUCCCCGACAUCUCUGCCCUCUGCCCAUCCCCCCAAGGGCAAGAUUUGCCAAAGCACAGGACACAUUGGCUCACACAUGGGGCACCCUGCCCCUGUCUUUUUGGAAAGGUCCAAUGGCAUAUGGCCAGCGGGUCGGGCAGGUGUGGCCGCUGGCCUGGGCUAAGCUGGCUGUGGCUGAGAGUCUGGGCGCAGAGACAGAAGGCGCCCCCUGCUGCAGAAGGAUCACAGUGUGGGCUCAUGGCAUUGGCUUUUUUGCGGUCCCAAGUCCUUCAUCUCCAUUGCCGGGCCCAUCUCGGGGGUCGGCAGAUGCGUGUCCCCUACUAGCAAAGACCUCCAGUCGGUUCUGCGGCUGCCUGUGAUGAGCCCUGCUCUGGCUAAGUGGAGGUGUUUGGCAGGGAGGAGUCCCCGGCUUAGUGUGAUUCCAGCUGUGGCCGAUUCUGGUGGGAUCCUGGCAAGGAGGAGGUUGCGUGUGGAUCUGGUGGAGGUGGACGGCCUGGCAGGGGGUGGGGUCUGCAACCCUAAGGAGCAGUGCCCCUCUCACUUGUCCCCCCGCCAGCAGACUGCUGCGUCGGCCUCCCCGGCCUGUGCCAUUCUGUGGCGAAGGUCCCUGUGUAGAGGAGGCUGGAGUGGGGGAGCUCAGCCCAGGCCAUGCCUCACCCUUCUUGGGUGCUCCAUGGGCAAAAGCUGAGGUCAGUUUGUGGAUCCUGGGAGCAGGAACCCUGCAGAGCCUGCCCCCCAGCUGGUGGCAGAGCAGGCAGUGGGGAGCUGCUGGGGCAGGAGGGAGUGACCUCCCUCCAAGACAGCCCCCAGUGGGGAUGGGAGGGUCUGCAGAGAUCUGGAGAGUCAAGUGUCAUGACCCAGGUGGGGCCAUGGAGCUGGGCUGGCCGGUGGAACUGUGUCCACCUGGACAUGCUCUGGGUGAGGCGCAGUCAGCGCUGGGAUGGCUAGAAGCGGCCUGUGCUGGGCGGGUCCUCGGGACACAGGGGCUGCCGCUGUCACAGAAGCCUGGCACAGAUUCUCUCUGGUUCUUAUGUUUCAUUCAUGCAGCCAUUCAGUCAAAGCUGAAGCUGGUGGGGUCCUGGCCAAACAGGACGCAGCAGUGCACCACCUGGGGGCUGCCCUCAGAGGCCCCGCGAGGGGAAUAGUGCCACAGGGGCCCAUGGGGAGGGCCUGUGGGUCACCCUGGGUGGUGGGUGGGCUCCUGGCUCCGCGGGGCCUCCGAGGGCAAGGUGGGGUUUCUCUGGCUGCCGGCUGUGGAAGCCGCUCAUGCGGAGGCCCAGCCGGGAGGCUGCAGGAGGCCGUGGGGAGGGCAGAGCCAGCUGCCUUCCCUGAUGGCUGUGGAGCUGCCCACGGGACCCCUCUCCUUGUCUGGGGCUCACUGGUGCCACAGGAAAAGGAAGCCCCGGUGCUGGAGCCUGCCCUGGCCCAGGCCUUGGUGCACAUCUCGGCAGCGUCACCCGACAGGUGAGGGAGGCAGCGUCACCCGACAGGUGAGGCCUCUGGACAGAUGAGGCCAUGUGGGGUUUCCCUGAAGAAGCAGAGCCCGGCUGCUGGGUGGGGGCUCCUCUUAGUCACUGACAGGGAGAGCUGUGCUUGUAAAACAUCCACCCAUUCCUGUGGAAGCUCUCGCGGUCCUGGGCAGGGUGAGGAGGGAGCAUUGGAGAGGCCAAGCUGGCCAGGAAGUUUGUGCCCCUGAGAAUUAGAGGGAGUCCUGUGCUCCAACUCGCAGCCGGGGCACGGAUCGGGGGCACGGAUCGGGAGCCCAGCCCUGCAGGCAGAGCCUCUGCACUGGACUCAGUCUCCGGAGUGGGGCUGGGCUCCUCACCGGGCCUUGCUCGGGGGACAACCUGUGGGGCUCAGGCCCCUGAGUCAGAGCAGGAGUCGGGGGCUUUGCUGUGGCCCCUCCUCACUGCUCACCUGCAGCCUCUCCCGGGCCAGGGUGUCUCCUGAACUGGCCUGAGAUGCAAAGCACUGGGUUGCAGUGCUGCCCAGGUGGAGGGCUGGCCUGUGAGGCCCAGGCUGGCCUGUGUCCUGGAGUUGGCAGGGCCCCCUCCCAUCCUCAGCCACAUCCACCCAGUCUCAGGGGUCCCUCCAGCCUCCUGGGACUGCCGUGUCCCCCACCUCUGCUUCAGGCAGUGUUCCUGGGCUGCCUCCUUCCCUGGCCAUGGGGUCCUAGUGGUUUAAUGAAAAUUGAGUGGUGGCCCUCCCCUCCCCGCCAGGCUGGAGUGUAGUGGUGCGAUCACAGCCAGCUGUAGCCUCCACCUUCUGAUUUUCCCUCUUAAUGUUCACAUCCAUUCUUCUUGUUAACGAGACUGUGCUGAAGCCCAGCAUGGUGGAGAGAGGCAGCCCACGGUGACUCACGUCUGCAGAGUGAGCUCUCGGGGGUCAGCGCCCAGACUGGGGAUUAGCAGUCCUGGGCCUCGAGCCCUGUGGCUGACUCCAUCCCUGCCUCCGGCAGCCUGGAUUUGCACCUUUGUAUAAACGGAGCCGCCUGGCAUGGCGUUUGCACUUGGCUACUUCCCUCCAUCUGCUGGUGAGCUCUGGCUUGUGCUCUGUGUGGCGAGUGGGUCCCUGCUUGGUUGGGACUCAGCCCCGCUUCAGGACCCCGUGGCCACUGAGGACCCAGGAACCUGCCUCUGCUCGAGUAUCCGGCCUCUGUCGUGAGUGCCUUGCGUGGCCAGGGCCACUUUUCCAGAGAAGGCUCUGUGGUGCUGUGUGGCCUCGCUGCACUGUCCCUGACGUGCAGGGCCCAAAGCUGGUGUCCCCCAGGAGCAGUGUCUGGGGACAGAUGCCUCCUGGUCCCGCUGGCCGAUGCCUGCUGGUCUUGUACGGCGCCUGCAUCGUGUUUGCCGUUUUUCUGUUGGGUUGUCUGACGUUUUCGUGUGGAUCAUAGGAGUUCCUCGCCCUGUGUGGACACGAGUCCUCUGAGGGACGCGUGUCACGGUGUCUGCUCACUUGCCACUGCCCGUCCAACCAUGUCCCGAGCAGCCCCGCCCAACAUGGACCCAGACCCCCAGGCGGGCGUGCAGGUGGGCAUGCGGGUGGUGCGCGGCGUGGACUGGAAGUGGGGCCAGCAGGACGGCGGCGAGGGCGGCGUGGGCACGGUGGUGGAGCUUGGCCGCCACGGCAGCCCCUCGACACCCGACCGCACAGUGGUCGUGCAGUGGGACCAGGGCACGCGCACCAACUACCGCGCCGGCUACCAGGGCGCGCACGACCUGCUGCUGUACGACAACGCCCAGAUCGGCGUCCGGCACCCCAACAUCAUCUGUGACUGCUGCAAGAAGCACGGGCUGCGGGGGAUGCGCUGGAAGUGCCGUGUGUGCCUGGACUACGACCUCUGCACGCAGUGCUACAUGCACAACAAGCAUGAGCUCGCCCACGCCUUCGACCGCUACGAGACCGCUCACUCGCGCCCUGUCACACUGAGUCCCCGCCAGGGCCUCCCGAGGAUCCCACUAAGGGGCAUCUUCCAGGGAGCGAAGGUGGUGCGAGGCCCCGACUGGGAGUGGGGCUCACAGGAUGGAGGGGAAGGGAAACCGGGCCGUGUGGUGGACAUCCGUGGCUGGGAUGUGGAGACAGGCCGGAGUGUGGCCAGCGUGACGUGGGCUGAUGGUACCACCAAUGUGUACCGUGUGGGCCACAAGGGCAAGGUGGACCUCAAGUGUGUGGGCGAGGCAGCGGGCGGCUUCUACUACAAGGACCACCUCCCAAGGCUCGGCAAGCCGGCGGAGCUGCAGCGCAGGGUGAGUGCUGACAGCCAGCCCUUCCAGCACGGGGACAAGGUCAAGUGUCUGCUGGACACUGAUGUCCUGCGGGAGAUGCAGGAAGGCCACGGCGGCUGGAACCCCAGGAUGGCGGAGUUUAUCGGACAGACGGGCACCGUGCAUCGUAUCACGGACCGCGGGGACGUGCGCGUGCAGUUCAACCACGAGACGCGCUGGACCUUCCACCCCGGGGCGCUCACCAAGGACACCAGGAAGGCAGGACAGCUUCGUGGGCGGGAGGGAGGCGGCUGGGCUAAGAUGCUCCUGCACCACUCCUUCUGGGUGGGCGACGUGGUCCGGGUCAUCGGCGACCUUGACACAGUGAAGCGGCUGCAGGCUGGGCAUGGCGAGUGGACGGACGACAUGGCCCCUGCCCUGGGCCGCGUCGGGAAGGUGGUGAAAGUGUUUGGAGACGGGAACCUGCGUGUAGCAGUCGCUGGUCAGCGGUGGACCUUCAGCCCCUCCUGCCUGGUGGCCUACCGGCCCGAGGAGGAUGCCAACCUGGACGUGGCCGAGCGCGCCCGGGAGAACAAAAGCUCACUGAGCGUGGCCCUGGACAAGCUUCGGGCCCAGAAGAGUGACCCAGAGCACCCGGGAAGGCUGGUGGUGGAGGUGGCGCUGGGUAACGCAGCCCGGGCUCUGGACCUGCUGCGGAGGCGCCCAGAGCAGGUGGACACCAAGAACCAAGGCAGGACCGCUCUGCAAGUGGCUGCCUACCUGGGCCAGGUGGAGUUGAUACGGCUGCUGCUACAAGCCAGGGCGGGCGUGGACCUGCCGGACGACGAGGGCAACACGGCACUGCACUACGCGGCCCUGGGGAACCAGCCCGAGGCCACCAGGGUGCUCCUGAGUGCUGGGUGCCGGGCGGACGCCAUCAACAGCACCCAGAGCACAGCACUGCACGUGGCCGUGCAGAGGGGCUUCCUGGAGGUGGUGCGGGCCCUGUGUGAGCGCGGCUGUGACGUCAACCUGCCCGACGCCCACUCGGACACGCCCCUGCACUCCGCCAUCUCGGCGGGCACUGGAGCCAGCGGCAUUGUCGAGGUCCUCACGGAGGUGCCAAACAUCGAUGUUACCGCCACCAACAGCCAGGGUUUCACCCUGCUGCACCAUGCCUCCCUCAAGGGUCACGCGCUAGCUGUGAGAAAGAUUCUGGCUCGGGCGCGGCAGCUGGUGGACGCCAAGAAGGAGGACGGCUUCACGGCGCUGCAUCUGGCUGCCCUCAACAACCACCGCGAGGUGGCCCAGAUCCUCAUCCGGGAGGGCCGCUGUGACGUGAACGUGCGCAACCGGAAGCUGCAGUCCCCGCUGCAUCUCGCCGUGCAACAGGCCCACGUGGGGCUGGUGCCGCUACUGGUGGACGCUGGGUGCAGUGUCAACGCCGAGGACGAGGAGGGGGACACAGCCCUGCACGUGGCGCUGCAGCGUCAUCAGCUGCUGCCCCUGGUGGCUGAUGGGGCCGGGGGGGACCCAGGGCCCUUGCAGCUGCUGUCCAGGACAUGGGGCGCCGGCUGCUGGGGCUGCCAGGUGCCAGGAGACGCCUCCCUCGGGCCUGCCCCGGCGCCCGCCCUCACCGGCGUCUGUCCUGCCGCCCAGCUACAGGCCUCGGGCCUCCCCGGCAGCGCGGAGCUGACGGUGGGCGCGGCGGUCGCCUGCUUCCUGGCGCUGGAGGGCGCCGACGUGAGCUACACCAACCACCGCGGUCGGAGCCCGCUGGACCUGGCCGCCGAGGGUCGCGUGCUCAAGGCCCUUCAGGGCUGCGCCCAGCGCUUCCGGGAGCGGCAGGCGGGCGGGGGCGCGGCCCCGGGCCCCAGGCAAACGCUCGGGACCCCCAACACCGUGACGAACCUGCACGUGGGCGCCGCGCCGGGGCCCGAGGCCGCUGAGUGCCUGGUGUGCUCCGAGCUGGCGCUGCUGGUGCUGUUCUCGCCGUGCCAGCACCGCACCGUGUGUGAGGAGUGCGCGCGCAGGAUGAAGAAGUGCAUCAGGUGCCAGGUGGUCGUCAGCAAGAAACUGCGCCCAGACGGCUCUGAGGUGGCGAGCGCCGCCCCCGCCCCCGGCCCGCCGCGCCAGCUGGUGGAGGAGCUGCAGAGCCGCUACCGGCAGAUGGAGGAACGCAUCACCUGCCCCAUCUGCAUCGACAGCCACAUCCGCCUCGUGUUCCAGUGCGGCCACGGCGCAUGCGCCCCCUGCGGCUCCGCGCUCAGCGCCUGCCCCAUCUGCCGCCAGCCCAUCCGCGACCGCAUCCAGAUCUUCGUGUGAGCCGCGCCGUCCGCCGCGCCCGAGCUGCCUUCGCGUGCCCCCGCCCUGUGUUUUAUAAAAAGAAAGAUUCUCGGA